GCACAGCCAAGAUGGCGGCGUCCGUGCGACAGGCACGCAGCCUACUAGGUGUGGCGGCGACCCUGGCCCCGGGUUCCCGUGGCUACCGGGCGCGGCCGCCCCCGCGCCGCAGGCCGGGACCCCGGUGGCCAGACCCCGAGGACCUCCUGACCCCGCGGUGGCAGCUGGGACCGCGCUACGCGGCUAAGCAGUUCGCGCGUUACGGCGCCGCCUCCGGGGUGGUCCCCGGUUCGUUAUGGCCGUCGCCGGAGCAGCUGCGGGAGCUGGAGGCCGAAGAACGCGAAUGGUACCCGAGCCUGGCGACCAUGCAGGAGUCGCUGCGGGUGAAGCAGCUGGCCGAAGAGCAGAAGCGUCGGGAGAGGGAGCAGCACAUCGCAGAGUGCAUGGCCAAGAUGCCACAGAUGAUUGUGAACUGGCAGCAGCAGCAGCGGGAGAACUGGGAGAAGGCCCAGGCUGACAAGGAGAGGAGGGCCCGACUGCAGGCUGAGGCCCAGGAGCUCCUGGGCUACCAGGUGGACCCAAGGAGUGCCCGCUUCCAGGAGCUGCUCCAGGACCUAGAGAAGAAGGAGCGCAAGCGCCUCAAGGAGGAAAAACAGAAACGGAAGAAGGAGGCGCGAGCUGCUGCAUUGGCUGCAGCUGUGGCUCAAGACCCAGCAGCCUCUGGGGCACCCAGCUCCUGAGGCUUUGUCCCUUCCCAAUAAAGCCUGCUACCUGGCAGUACCCCUGAAGAGAUCUGCGUCCUCUCAAGGUGUGCCUCUCUGGGUCCCCUGGUUCCUCCCCCAAUACUUAAGAGCUGGGGAAUCCCCCACUUGGCUGUACUCAAAAGGGGACAGGGACUCUAGGCCCUGCUGACUAACUGGGGCUUCAGUGGGAGGAAAAGGGGGGUGUACAAUGGGCAAAUAAUGGAGAAGCAGAUGGCAGAAGAGAAGAAGGCUUCUGUUUACCAACAUUCAUCUCCAGUAAUUAGCCAAUUACAAGGCUGGUGGGGGGGGAAGUAUAGCCAAAACAGACUGUGGUGAUGAUGGUGGGGGCCGGGGAGAAGCAGUCCUUGUAACGUUGGGCUGGGGUCCACUGCCUGGAAAUGACACACUGGGGGAGGAGACACCGGAAGCCUCAAUCUGCAGGGACUCACAGACUCCUCUCCCCCUUCCAGGCACCCGUCACCAUGCCUGCCUGUGCCCAGCCAGCCCCCCAAGACCCAGACAGGUGGGCGCGGGGAGCCCCAGCAGGCACAGACCAUAGGGCUAGUUUUUAAAACUUUAUUCACUUCAAAACCUUUAUCAGAGACACGGUUCUGUUCUGGGGUGGGGGUGGCCUUGACAAUGAGCUGAUGUUAGCCCUUCUCCAGGCUGGAGGCCAAGGCCAGACUGGGGAGGGGGCCUUGGGCCUUUCAGGACUUGCCCUAGAUGGAAAGAUUUGGGCCACUCCAAUGGAGGAUCAAAGUUGGGGCUCCAGCUUCCCCUCAUCCUAGAAGAGGAUGGGGGGGGGUCCUCAGGGGUUUUUCGGAGGAUGGAGAGGCAAGCAGCCGCCUUUCCGUCUGGCUGCAGAGAGCUGGGACAGAGGCCAAGAGGGGCCCAUCUGUCGCCUCCCAGUCCUGCCAGCUUCUCUGAGCAGGCUGGGCUGGGGAGGAGGACGGGGGGACAGCUGUCUGGCCCGGGAGAUGGGAACAGGGGCCACUUUAGGAGGACAGGAAGCUGGACUGUUUGCUUGUUUUUUUAAGAUUUUUGAUUUUUUUUUCCAUUUCUUAAAUAAACAUGAAUAUAUAUAUA